GUUGUGAGCUGCGGCAGAGACUGGUGGCUGGAGGAGACGCCGGCGCUGGAGAGUGCGCUGCGCCGCCCGCCGCUGAGGGACCGCGGGGUUAGCCACUGCUGGCUGCUUCCAGUGUUCGCCGAGAGGUACCGGGGGUGACAGCUCCGGGACCGGCCGAAAGGUGUGGAAAUUAAAAGAACACACAUAUUUUGACUGGGGCUUUGAUCAACCAAAUGCUAAAAAGGCUGGAGUGCAAUGGUGCGAUCUCGGCUCACUGCAACCUCCGCCUCCCGGGUUCAAGUGAUUCUCCUGUCUCCUGGGUUCAAGUGAUUCUCCUGCCUCAGCCUCCUGAGUAGCUGGGACUACAGGCGUCCACAACCACGCCCAGCUAAUCUUUGUAUUACUUUAUUGUAUAAAAUGGGAAGGCAAAAGCUAGCAAAUUUCAUGUGGAAGCCCAAAAGAUACAUUCUGAAUGCAUCUCACACUCCUAAGAUGCCCUCCUGCAAAUCAUUUAUACAUAGGAAGUGUUUACAUUUGGUGUAGUUACGGAGACCAGUAAUUGGAGAGUUCCCAGAAAAUCCAGAGGAAGUCAAGAUGCCCAAAAGUCAGGAGGCAGCAGGCUGAAGCUGUUUGGAAAGAUCUAUGAGAUAGUCUCUCUUACAUACAGAGCAGUAAACAAAUAUCUCAUUGCUGUUGAAGACUUUGUAAUACAAGGUGAUUUUAUAGGUGUUCUAGUCCAGGAUUUUCCAUUUUUUAUUGGGUAAAAGUAGUGGAGAGGAAGACCUCUUUUGUCAGUGAACAAAUCAAGGAGCCAACUAUGAAAAUAAGGGGCAGAUAAUAGCAUAAAAAGACAGACCCUUAAUUGAUACAAAGCUUAAUCAAUUUUAUAUUAAUACUUAACUCACUGUUCUCAAAUUUAUCUAAUAAAUAUUAGAUAGAAUAAAAUCAUUGAAUACAUAAAACAAAGUAUACUUUUAUAUUUGUUUUUCUACUUGUCCAUUCUAGCCAAAGGGAAAUUCUUAGUUCUUACAAUGUGCUAUUUUGUUUUGUAUUCUGAACAAAUUUUCAUUUAAACAUUGAGAAAGUGAAAAUGUAUGCAGGAAGAAGCUCACGAUUUCCAUUGUUGUUAAUACCAAUAAUUGUAUCACUAGUCAAAGUCACAAUCACUUGUGUGAAUUUUUUGAACCUGAAAUGCAACAGGAAUUUAAACUAGAUUAAGCUGGAAUGAAUAGUAGGUUCUUGAUUUGGGUACCUGACUUGUAGCUAAUUCAACCAUAAUUUGAAUCUAGAUUAAUAAGGCAUUAAGAUUAAAAUAUGAGUUAUAUUCCAUGUCAUCACAGUUUAUGUUUAUCAUAAUUGAAAUGUUCCCUUUUUUAAUUACUUGUGAUAUUACAUACAUUGAACUUUUUGAAGUUUCACCAACAACAAAAAAUUGACAUUCAGGUACAGUAGUGAUCUCUCUUGAUAUGGGGGAUACAUUUCUGUUUAUAAAAUGGUUAUUGAGAUAACUUCAAAUUAAAAGCAUAUUUGAUAGAUACGCUACUGCUCAUGUGUGGGAGCCUGGAAUUUGGAAGUCAUUCUAUGCAUUGUAAAUGGAGUUGUAAAUGUUAAGCUGUGUGUAUGCACAUGCAUCCAGACAUCCACACAAAUAUAUGGGCAACUGUAACCCAAGUUGGGUGACGUAUAAUGAAGCAAACAUGAACUCUGAGUAAUCAGAAAAAUCUUAAAAGAGAUGGGAAGAAAUCCAUUUUUUUUUAGUUAGUGAUAAUAAAUUUUAAAACUAAUAAAAUAUUUUAAACUCAGAUAUAUUUUUAUUCAUUUAGGUAUUAAAAUUAAUAAAAUGAAAUAGAGCUUUUAUUUGUUCUCAGGCAAGUCUGUUACCUAAAAUCUGCAAAACAUAAUUGGGUCGAAGUUAAAAAUCUAGCUUGUUUGGACCAUAACAUACAUGUAGAGGAAAAUAUUUCCUCAAAUUUAAGAGAAACUAAUUUUCCUAACUAAAUUUGUGGGAGUUACUUUGUUGACAUUUACUCCGAAACCAGCCAUUGCCACAUAAAGAAGAUCCCUAAUAGUCAUUUCUCAACAAUUAUAUAGUCAACUGAUGUAACAAUGGUACUAAUAUUGGGACGCAGACUAAACAGAGAGGAUCUUGGGGUGCGUGAUUCCCCAGCAACUAAGCGAAAAGUUUUUGAAAUGGACCCCAAAUCUCUGACAGGUCAUGAGUUUUUUGACUUCUCUUCAGGAUCAUCCCAUGCCGAAAACAUACUCCAGAUAUUUAAUGAAUUUCGUGAUAGCCGCUUAUUCACAGAUGUUAUCAUUUGUGUGGAAGGAAAAGAAUUUCCUUGCCAUAGAGCUGUGCUCUCAGCCUGUAGCAGCUACUUCAGAGCUAUGUUUUGUAAUGACCACAGGGAAAGCCGAGAAAUGUUGGUUGAGAUCAAUGGUAUUUUAGCUGAAGCUAUGGAAUGUUUUUUGCAGUAUGUUUAUACUGGAAAGGUGAAGAUCACUACAGAGAAUGUACAGUAUCUCUUUGAGACAUCAAGCCUCUUUCAGAUUAGUGUUCUCCGUGAUGCAUGUGCCAAGUUCUUGGAGGAGCAACUUGAUCCUUGUAAUUGCUUAGGAAUCCAGCGCUUUGCUGAUACCCAUUCACUCAAAACACUCUUCACAAAAUGCAAAAAUUUUGCGUUACAGACUUUUGAGGAUGUAUCCCAGCACGAAGAAUUUCUUGAGCUUGACAAAGAUGAACUUAUUGAUUAUAUUUGUAGUGAUGAACUUGUUAUUGGUAAAGAGGAGAUGGUUUUUGAAGCCGUCAUGCGUUGGGUCUAUCGUGCCGUUGAUCUGAGAAGACCACUGUUACACGAGCUCCUGACACAUGUGAGACUCCCUCUGUUGCAUCCCAACUACUUUGUUCAAACAGUUGAAGUGGACCAAUUGAUCCAGAAUUCUCCUGAGUGUUAUCAGUUGUUGCAUGAAGCAAGACGGUACCACAUACUUGGGAAUGAAAUGAUGUCCCCAAGGACUAGGCCACGCAGGUCCACUGGCUAUUCUGAGGUGAUAGUUGUCGUUGGAGGAUGUGAGCGAGUUGGAGGAUUUAAUCUUCCAUACACUGAGUGCUACGAUCCUGUAACAGGAGAAUGGAAGUCUUUGGCUAAGCUUCCAGAAUUUACCAAAUCAGAGUAUGCAGUCUGUGCUCUAAGGAAUGACAUUCUUGUUUCAGGUGGAAGAAUCAACAGCCGUGAUGUCUGGAUUUAUAACUCACAGUUAAAUAUUUGGAUCAGAGUUGCCUCUCUCAAUAAAGGCAGAUGGCGUCACAAAAUGGCUGUCCUCCUUGGUAAAGUAUAUGUUGUCGGUGGCUAUGAUGGGCAAAACAGACUUAGCAGCGUAGAAUGUUAUGAUUCCUUUUCAAAUCGAUGGACUGAAGUUGCUCCCCUUAAGGAAGCCGUGAGUUCUCCUGCAGUGACUAGCUGUGUAGGCAAACUGUUUGUGAUUGGUGGAGGACCUGAUGAUAAUACUUGUUCUGAUAAGGUUCAAUCUUAUGAUCCAGAAACCAAUUCUUGGCUACUUCGUGCAGCUAUCCCAAUUGCCAAAAGGUGUAUAACAGCUGUAUCCCUAAACAACCUGAUCUAUGUUGCCGGUGGACUGACCAAGGCAAUAUACUGUUACGAUCCAGUUGAAGAUUACUGGAUGCACGUACAGAAUACAUUCAGCCGUCAGGAAAACUGUGGUAUGUCUGUGUGUAAUGGUAAAAUAUAUAUCCUGGGCGGAAGACGGGAAAAUGGAGAAGCCACAGACACUAUUCUCUGUUAUGAUCCUGCAACAAGUAUCAUCACAGGGGUAGCUGCAAUGCCCAGGCCAGUGUCCUAUCAUGGCUGUGUGACUAUUCAUAGAUACAAUGAGAAAUGCUUUAAACUCUGAAGACAGGAUACCUCACCGAAGAAGCCACACUGAUCCAAGAUGGGAGGUUUUAAAAACUCUACAGUGGGAACUUCACAUAUCUCCUUUGUGCCAUAUGCAAAAAAUAGUAAAAAUAAUAAUUUGGUGCCUUUCUCCUCAAAAUAUCAAUCUUUCAAACUAUAAUAAAGCCUUUCCUAUAAUUGAAAAAAAAAACUUUUUUGUUAAAGGUAAUGGUGGUUGUUACUUGGCCUUUGAAGAGUGUACCUUUGUAAGUAUUUGUAAGAAGUCUAUGUGAAUUAGGAAAUGUCUGUCUGCAUACCUUUUAGGAGCGUGUGAAUGGUGUCUUCACUUAUUAUGUAUGUUUAUCUGUAUGUAUAUUCCUUAUUUUGUCAUAUAUGUAGAGAAAAUUGCAUGACUUGAGGCAUCAUUUAGGUUGAAGAAGUUAAUGCUUAGGAUGCAUUCUAGGAGAAAAAAUCAGUUUUAAAAACCUUUGUUGUUAACAAAGUAUAUCCAGAUUGGUUAAUUUUAUUGAAGGGUUUUUUUCUGUAAUUGAUAAAAAUGUAAUGACAACAAUUCAGGCAUCAUAAAAUACUGAACUAUUGUGACUUUAUUCUUAGAAUUGCUGUCUUACAUUAAACAUGUUUUUAGGGGGAAGUUAGGUAGGAGAUAGAAAAAUAAGUGCCCCUACAAGGGGGAUUAAAAUUACAAGUUAAUUCCUAAGAGAAAAAUGGAAUGGCCUUUGAAGGAAAAAUGACCCACUAUGGCUCUCAAAGUUUUUAUGCAUCAUCUCUUCAAUCCUCUAAGAAAGCCUCUUUUCUUAACUUGAUAAAGCAGUGGAAACCCAUUUUGCAAUAUUGUUUUGUGAAAAACAGGGACAGACAGCCAGGUACAGAGACUCACACCUGUACUCCCAACUACUCAGCAGGCUGGGGCAGGAGGAUUGCUUGAGCCCAGGAGUCUGAGGCUACAGUGAGCUAUGAACGCACACGGCACCCUAGCCUGGGCAACAGGUUGCGACACUGUCUCAAGAGAAAAGAAAAAGAAAAAUAGGGAUAGGUUUUCCUUCCUAGCCCAGUAGAGUUUGACCUCAUUAGUAUGGUGCUUUGGGUGAGGACCUCUUCCUUGAUUAUCCCACUUUCUAGUGAACAGCUAAAAUUCCUGAGAGUCUCUACUGUUAAGGUACCUUUAAUAGGAUAAAGCAGGGACCACCUAUCUCAGUGGGUCCAUUUUUCUUUUAAAAUUAGUUAUCUGAAAAAACUUAGCAGUAGUUCCCAUCUUUAAGGUAAGUCUUUCAUUUGGUCCCCAUUGUGUAAAAUACUAAUCAACAUUUUCAAGCUUCUGUACAACAGACUGCUUUUGUCUAGAUUUCUCAACUCCACUUUAUAAAGCUUAUCAGUUUUCAGAGAGGAAUGUGAAUUUUUUUUCUAAUGCAAAUAAAUGGAUAUGGCAGGAACUACAGCAUAAGUGAUUAUUGUGAUUCUGGGUGGACGGAUAUAAUUUACAACAUUUAGGGAUGUUCUAGGUAGCCUGCUGUAGUUUGACUUCCAGUCACUGUUGUCUUUCACAUUAUAAUUUGUAUAUUUCUUGUGAUAGAAGGGAUGAUGCAAAUAUGUAAUUAAAGUGUCACCAGAUUUCUGUUAAAACCAAGGUUGAAAUAAAAAGCCUAACAUUGGUAAGCUACAUUGUUUUCUCAUUUUAGAAUGAUUCAGAGAUUUCAGAUAGACAUUUUUUAAACUUUAAUGCUUAGCUAGAAUCUACAUUCUGAGGAAAACUCUAAAAAACUUAAAAAUUUUUAGGGAAUUUUUAUUUUUCAAAUCAUAAUUUUAAAAUGAUAGAUACCAUUUUGUGAUAACAACAAUUCAGAAAACAAUUUUCUAUCCUCUUAGUUGAAAGAAUGUAGGUACAGUUUGGAUACUUGUACUUUAAUUUUAGAGUAAACAUCUGCAUUAUACUCUUAUAGAUAAUAGAAUUAUUUAGUUAAGAAAUUCUUUACAGUAAAUGAGAUAAUGUGUGAAAAAGUAUUUUGUAAAUGCUGAGGAUUCUACAAAUGAUAGUUGUUAUUUUCAUGUGUAUUUGUAAGAUCAUGUCCAUUUCAUGAAUAUAGGACUUCACAUAAAAAAAGACUUUCUCAAGACAACUUUAUAUUCUAGUAUUUUUCUGUUGUAAAAAGUAUUAACUAUUUACUUUUAUUUUGUUAUACAUUUAUUUUAAUAUCCAUGUGUUUAUUAUAGUAAAUUUGAAAUGAAAUCCUGAAAAACAGAAUUUUUUUAAACACAGACCUCACACCAAUAUUAAUUUUUUCUCUACAUAAUUUAAAACUACAUAAAUUAAGUACUUAAAAUUUAUAUUGAAGGCCACCAAGAACUUAGGUUGAAUCUUAGAAAAUUUAAAUAACUAUUUUUAAAGUUACCCAACUUAAUAUUUUAAUUUUUUAAUAUUUAUCUUCCUUUACUAAUUCUUGAUAAAUAAUAGCAUUAGACUUGAUAAAAUAAAAAAGAAUUUUAGAGUAGAAUUAAUAUAUCAAAAGGGGUAUAUCAACCAAAUUGGUGUCAGAUUGUAUUCAUUCUCUCAUCACAUAAAGAUUUUUCUUUUGAUAGGUGAUGCUCAUAUGAACCUUUGGUUUAGAAUCUAUAUAUGUACAUGUGUAUGUAUGUAGAUAGUAUGGUUGUAUACACACAUAUAUACCAAACACCAUGAAUUUUAGCAGUCUGUGAUGAUCAGCAAAAAAGCACAUAAAGUAAAAAUUAGUUGACCAUGCUAAAUUCAAUUCUGGAAUUUUUUUUUAUUUGGGCAUUUCUAGAACUUUUUACAUUUGAAAGUACAUGAUGAGUAUUAGUAACGAUGACUUAUGUAUAAUCAGAAUCUUUAUGACAAUUUAGUUUUACAAGGUCAGAAGAGAUGAGUUUGCUAAACCCAGCUGUGAUACCUCAGUUGGAAAGGGAAUUCAAAGGUAUGCUUUGUAGAACAGAAAAGUAUAGUUUUUUUUUCAUGAACUUUAAUCAUUUUCUGUUUUUCCUCUAUGUGAGUCAGCUACAAAAGUGGUCUAAUUUUUACAACAGUAGAACUUCCUCCUUUUCUACUGUAAUCUUCCCACUGACUUUACUGCACAGGUAUGAAAUACUAGUGUAUUGGAUCUUCAGUAACCUUUUUAUUUCCUAGAUGAUUGAAAUAUAGGUAUUUACUCCAUUUAAACCAGGUGAUAAGAUGAUGUAAAUACUCAGGGAGGGUAUUAACUUGUUACUUUUGCUCGUUUGGGGUGUAAAGUGCCAUGACUGAAUAAUCUUCAAUUCAUGAUUCUAGAGUAAGUUUAAUUUGGAAAAAGGGGCUUCACACAUGGUGGUGGUUGAACAUUGAUUCUUUUAUACUUAAAAAGAUGAAAAUGUUUUGUGGACUGAUACAUUUUAUCUUACUGAAUAUGAAUUGUUUAUGUAUCUCUACUGUCAAAUAGCCUUUUUGAAACUCAGGAAAGACAAAGGUUCAAUUACACCACUUUUGUCAAUAAGCAAACCAGGUAUUUUUUUUUUCUCCUGUUGUCUGGAUAUGGCAAUAGAUUUUUUAAAUUGCUGUGAGAACCCAUAUAUGAAAAGAGAGGAGUUGAAUUGUGUGUGCCUUUUAUGUCUUGAGAUUUAUAUGUGGAAAAGACGACAUCUACUUCAAACUGUAUUUUUUUCGUUUUUUUUUUUUUUUGGGGAAGGGGGGAGAACGGGGUCUUGCUCUGUCGCCCAGGCUGGAGUGCAGUGGCGCGAUCUCAGCUGACUGCAACCUCCACCUCCCGGGUUCAAGGGAUUCUGCCUCAGCCUCCCGAGUAGCUGAGACCACAGGUGCGUGCCACCACACCCGGCUAAUUUUUUUGUAUUUUUAGUAGAGACGGGGUUUAGUAGAGACGGAUCACUCCUGACCACGUGAUCCGCCCACCUCGGCCUCCCAAAGUGCUGGGAUUACAGGCGUGAGCCACCACCCCCGGCCUGUAUUUUCAGAGAGGAGAGCUUGGUGUUUUUGUGGUGCCAAGUGGUAAGAUAAUGUCUCUUUGAGGCUUCCUAUGGACUGCCUUUAUUUUAGUAAACUCAAGACACCAGUUAACCUCAACAGAGUUUUGGCCUUAUUAGAAUUUGUUGUGCAUCUUAUUGAAAGCCAGGUUUACAUCACCUCACCCCAUUAUUCUUUUUAGUUAAAUAAAUUUACCAUGCCAAGUAACCAGAAUGGAGCAAAUUGGUUGAUCUUUAAGGCAGUAGGUUUGACUAGCUAGCUAUCAUUAUUGUCACAUCUAAUGCUAGGCACCAGAAACCAUUUGAGCCAGGAGUGUGAAUGAAUAAUUCCAGAGACACUUUAGACAUUUUUUAAUGUUUUAUAUGAACAUUUUACAUUUGUGUGAUUGCCUUAGAUAUUAAAUUUUCCUAGUGCUGAUAAAAACAGCAACAUUCAUAACUUAUUUUAUAUAUUGUUCCAAAGAAAAGAAUUUGUUUUAAUGGUUUCAAAAUAACUGCACCUGAAUUUGUUUAUGUGCCUUAAGUUCUCUAGUGCUAUUUCAACUUUUUUUUCAAUCUAAAUGAAGCUUACCUUAGAUAAGGUUCAUAUUUGUUUCCUAUAGAGUAAAUAAACUUCCCCUUCUUAAAUUGUGUAAUAAGCACCAACGUGUGGUUGCUUGGCAGAAUGAGAAUGUUAAGGGAGAUUGUUGGAUGUUUGGAGUUUCAUUAUAUUUUUUGUUUUUAUUUUUUGAUACCUAGGUGCUUUUUAAAAUAUUCAGACAAAUAUCUAUCUUACAUUGAUUAAACCCGUGUAAAUUCAUUUGCAGUAUCUACAUCGAAUGUCAAAAAAGUAUACUUAUUUUUGUUCCAUACUUAUGUACAAUUUUUUCCCUCUUCAGGCUUUUUCAUUUACCUUUUUGAAAAAGCACUUACUCUCCCCUUCCCUAUCACCCCUCCCCCAAGGUUUCUUUAUUUAAAUUUUUAUUGAGAGUUGUUGGAGCUCUAAGACAAUACAAAUUUAGAGUUGAACAAAAGUAUAAUCUGCUUUACAACUAGUAUAGACCUAAGGUCAUUUGCUUUCAAUUAGAGGCUCCAGAGUCUUCAUAGUGGAAAGAAUGCUUUGUAUUUAAUUGUUCUUAGUUAAGUUGUAGCACGUGAAUACUUACUUACAUGUUUUGUUUAAAUAUACUUCUUGCAUAGUUUAAUUUUUUAAAAGUUGUAUCUAAUAAAAUGUCUUUUAACCAUUAUUACUUGACUAUAUGGUUGUAUUAAAUUUUGUUUACGAAAAA